CUUUUCUUUGGCAAGAUGGCGGAGUACGACUUGACUACUCGCAUCGCGCACUUUUUGGAUCGGCAUCUAGUCUUUCCGCUUCUUGAAUUUCUCUCUGUAAAGGAGAUAUAUAAUGAAAAGGAAUUAUUACAAGGUAAAUUGGACCUUCUUAGUGAUACCAACAUGGUAGACUUUGCUAUGGAUGUAUACAAAAACCUUUAUUCUGAUGAUAUUCCUCAUGCUUUGAGAGAGAAAAGAACCACAGUGGUUGCACAACUGAAACAGCUUCAGGCAGAAACAGAACCAAUUGUGAAGAUGUUUGAAGAUCCAGAAACUACAAGGCAAAUGCAGUCAACCAGGGAUGGUAGGAUGCUCUUUGACUACCUGGCGGACAAGCAUGGUUUUAGGCAGGAAUAUUUAGAUACACUCUACAGAUAUGCAAAAUUCCAGUACGAAUGUGGGAAUUACUCAGGAGCAGCAGAAUAUCUUUAUUUUUUUAGAGUGCUGGUUCCAGCAACAGAUAGAAAUGCUUUAAGUUCACUCUGGGGAAAGCUGGCCUCUGAAAUCUUAAUGCAGAAUUGGGAUGCAGCCAUGGAAGACCUUACACGGUUAAAAGAGACCAUAGAUAAUAAUUCUGUGAGUUCUCCACUUCAGUCUCUUCAGCAGAGAACAUGGCUCAUUCACUGGUCUCUGUUUGUUUUCUUCAAUCACCCCAAAGGUCGCGAUAAUAUUAUUGACCUCUUCCUUUAUCAGCCACAAUAUCUUAAUGCAAUUCAGACAAUGUGUCCACACAUUCUUCGCUAUUUGACUACAGCAGUCAUAACAAACAAGGAUGUUCGAAAACGUCGGCAGGUUCUAAAAGAUCUAGUUAAAGUUAUUCAACAGGAGUCUUACACAUAUAAAGACCCAAUUACAGAAUUUGUUGAAUGUUUAUAUGUUAACUUUGACUUUGAUGGGGCUCAGAAAAAGCUGAGGGAAUGUGAAUCAGUGCUUGUGAAUGACUUCUUCUUGGUGGCUUGUCUUGAGGAUUUCAUUGAAAAUGCCCGUCUCUUCAUAUUUGAGACUUUCUGUCGCAUCCACCAGUGUAUCAGCAUUAACAUGUUGGCAGAUAAAUUGAACAUGACUCCAGAAGAAGCUGAAAGGUGGAUUGUAAAUUUGAUUAGAAAUGCAAGACUGGAUGCCAAGAUUGAUUCUAAAUUAGGUCAUGUGGUUAUGGGUAACAAUGCAGUCUCACCCUAUCAGCAAGUGAUUGAAAAGACCAAAAGCCUUUCCUUUAGAAGCCAGAUGUUGGCCAUGAAUAUUGAGAAGAAACUUAAUCAGAAUAGCAGGUCAGAGGCUCCUAACUGGGCAACUCAAGAUUCUGGCUUCUACUGAAGAACCAUAAAGAAAAGAUGAAAAAAAAAACUAUCAAAGAAAGAUGAAAUAAUAAAACUAUUAUAUAAAGGGUGACUUACAUUUUGGAAACAACAUAUUACGUAUAAAUUUUGAAGAAUUGGAAUAAAAUUGAUUCAUUUUAUCUUGCUGUCAGUUUUCUUGCAUGUGCAAGUUUGUGUUUUUUUAACUUUCUUUUUUGGAAUAAUUAUAUUCAGAGGAAUUUGCAAAAAUAGUACAGAGAAGUCCCUGUAGGCUGAACCCUGUUUCCCUCAAUUUUUUCACUUUGUCUUACUAUGGUACAGUAUCAAAACCAGGAUGUUGACAUUGGUACAAUGUGUGUACAAAUAGCUCCCUACCAUUUUAUCACGUGUAGAUUUGUGUAACCAUCACUGCAGCCAAGAUAGAGAACUAUCAUCAUGAUCUCCCUCAUGCUACCUUUUUGUAGCCAUACCUACUCCCAACCAACUCUAACCCUAGGAACCACUAAUCUGUUCCUCAUCGCUAUAUUUUGUCAUUAUGAGAAUGUUAUAUAAAUGGAAUUACAUAAUACACAACCUUUGAGAUUAGCUUUUUUCAUUCAUCACAAUGCUCUUGAGAGCCAUCCAAGUUGAGAGAUAGAUAUAUAUAUAUAUAUGAUCAGUAGUUAAUUCCUUUUUUAUUGCCAAAUAG